UCUUGACCUUGUGAUCUGCCCGCCUUGGCCUCCCAAAGUGCUGGGAUUACAGGCAUGAGCCACUGCUCCCGGCCAAAACACACCUGCAUUUUUGGCAAAGAAGAUAACUCUAUUUGUUAAGUGACUAUUAGAGGGAAUUCUCCAAGCUUCUAGGAGUUACAGAGAGUGAAGAAAGGAAAUGCCCUGAUGGUUUUACUUCUAAUUUCAGAUUAAUACCUGACUGAUCUGGGUGGAAAUUUAUAUUUUCUGCUUUGUAAAACAGUAGAAGUCAGAUUUUUUAACCUUCAGUUUUUAUUGGGCCAAACAAGAUCCCUGAUCUGGGUAAGAUGAGAAAGCCUCUUGCUACAGGCUACUUAUGAAAGGAGUAAGGAGAGGAACACACCCUUCUUUAAGCUAAAGAUUACUUGGAUAAUCUGGCUAAUUAAUCAGUGCUUUUUUUUUUUAAUGAGUAGCUUUAUAUUUAGCAUUUCUAUAUCUUGACUCUUAACCCUAAGGAGGUUUAAAAAAAUAGCAGUGCCAGGGUCCUAUCCCAGACCAAUUAAAUCACAAUAUCAAGGUGGACCUAGACAAGAAAUAAAAACAAUCAGUGUCCCAGGAAGGCUUCAUGUUUUCUCCUCAUACUGCUAUUCUGUGUCUUUUAUUGCUAAUCAUGCUGAACUUUCUAAUGAAAUGCUUUGGGGAAAUAAUAAAGGACACUGUUCCAUAUGCUUUAGUCAGAAGGAUAGAUUUAAAUGGCAAAGUUGAUAAAGAUAUUGCUGCGUAUUGAUAUCAUAUAUAUGUUAUCUACAGCCUACUUUUGGUCCUGACAGUGUGGAACACUGGAUAAAGGUAAGGAUAUUUCAAAUUUAGAAUAAAAAGAGUAUUAAGAGUCAAGCAUAAUCAGAUGGAAAAGAAAUAUGAAUAGAUCUCCACUUUGCACAUACUCUGCUAUUUUUAUUCCCGUGUGACUAUGUAAGUUGCCUUAAUUUUAUACUUUUUAGUAUUUUUUUUCAUAAUUCUGUUGCCUCUCAUGAUACCAUUUAAGUAGGAAUGACAAGAAAACAGGUGUGUAGACUUCGUUUCAAAUGCCAUGAGUAUCACAUGAAGAGGAUUAAAGGAGUUGUGAAAAGAAGCCUUGGGAGAGGAUAUGGUGGCCUUCCUCAGAUGUUGGAAAGACUGCACUGUAGUUACAAUGACCUAGGGACUAAUGGGUGAAAACUACGUGUGCAUCACAAAUAAGAAUUUUCUAAUGACUAGUCCAUCCAAAAGUGGACUGGGUGUUCUUAUAGAGAUGUGUUUUCUACCACUGAAGCUAUUUUAAUGGACUCUAACUGGUCACUUAAUGUUAGGCUAAUGAACAAUAUGUUUGAGGAUUCAGUGAAGGGGAGAUUGUGUUAGAUAACCUCUGACAUCUCUUCCAGGCCUGAGAUAUGUAUUUUUGAGUCUGAGUACCAUUUAAUUUGAAAGUGCCAUUAAAUCAUUUCAGGUGUGUGCUUCUGCGUGUCAGUUUAGCAACUUGCCAUAUUCAAUUCAUCGUGUACCACAUGUUUCAAAAUCAUGCAGCAUUUUCCCGGGAAAAGACCAUUCUGACAGUAUUUUGAAGAGUGAUUACUCAUCUAAAUUGACAUGCAUCAUGAGCACCAGAUCCCAGAUAGAUAUAAUAGAUCCUAGGCCAGAUGUAAUAAUUUUUAAGCAUUUAUUUAUUCAGCUGGUAUUUGAGUGCCUACUAAGUACUAGCCCACUGUGUUGGGUGUUGGAGCUAAAACAGAGCAGGUACAGUCCCUGCCCUCCCAGGGUUUACAGUCCAGUGGAGAAUAAACAACUUACUAAAGCUCAUGAGAGAAUUAAAGAUGUAAUGGAAGUAUGUGGUGAGAGGCACUAAUUUAAAUGGAGUCAGGGGAAGCUUCCUGGCUACUGCAGAAAGCCUAACUUAGAUGACGACUAAAGUGGAUCUACCAUCAUGAAUGCUAGUCUCUAGGAAGGCCACUCCUCUAUCUAGUAAGACUAGCUUGCAUGUGAGUGUUGAGAGUCCCAGUGCCAAGUCCCUGCAGGGCUUAGUCACACAGUUAGUUACCAUCUCUUCAGAGGCAAAGAUUUAACUAAAACAGGAAGAUAAAAUUUUGCUCUGAUUUGUCUGUGACAUUGUCCGUUUUCAUAUAGUUUUCAGCCAGCUUGACUCAAUUUUUAUCAUCUUUUAUCAUUCCUCUAACAUUUCUGCAUUGGCUCUGUCUCCAUUAUGUCAUCAAAUCUGUCUUGAAAAAAACCAAUAAGUCUUUAUUUGAUCCUGUAAUCUAUUCUGAUUCCUGAACGAUUUCUUUUUCAUAUCUAAUGUUUUGGAUACAUAACCUGGACUCCUUGCCUUUGUAUUUUUCUUGUCCUCUUGUGUCCACAGUUAUUCUCCUGCGUCCUAAUUUCUUACCAUUCCACAGAAACUGUUGUCAUAAAUGACUUCCUGACCAAAUCCAGUAGUCUUUUGAUAGUCCUCAAACUUUUUCAGGUUACAUUGACAUAGUUACCAUUGCUUUAUUCUAGAAAUCCUCUCCUCCAUGGUCUUUUUGUAACUGUUUUUUUCCUGCUGCUUCUAAUACUUCCUUGUUCACUUCUCUGUCUUCUUUUCUUAUUUCAUUGCUAACUCUGGGUGUACCCUAAACAGUUAUAACCUCUGGACCGAAGACUUCAAAGUCCACUUGAGUGGACCACCCUUUCAAAAUCAGCUGAGACCUCUUUAUGUGAAAGAAGGGGAGAAUAUAUGGAAAGGGUAUGGAGUAUAGUAAAAAUUGAGAAAGGCCUCUCUUCAGAACAGAAAAGGAAGAUUUCUCAGUGGCACUGGGGACAUGGCUGAAGCAGUUAACCAUAAUUAAUUUUUAAAUAUAUAUUUUAAAUAGAGAUGGGGUUUCACUAUGUUGCCCAGGCUAGUCUCAAACUCCUGGGCUCAAGCAAUCCACUGGGCUCAGCCUCCCAAAGUGCUGGGAUUACAGGCGUGAGCCACCAUGCCUGGCCCAUAAUAUUUUAUGGUACUAAAAAUAGGUAGAUCAGAUUGAUCCAGACUUGGAGGUUUUCUCUGGAACAGCCAAGGAACAAGGGGUUCGAGGAUGCAGUAAGAUAGUAGCUGCAUAUCCACACUGAGUAGGAAAGGAAGGAACCCUUUCAAGGACUCAAGUUAGAAGAGGGAGGUGUACAGUGACUAGAAGACUUGGUUAGGUCCAACUUCAGUGUCAUAGGAGUAGGGAGAAUGAAACAGGGAGAUGGAUCAGAGGUUGAUGUUGGAGAAGGGGUUAUCAGUUUGGUUUGAGCAAUGGAAAAUGUUGUGAACCAUGCUUUGUGACAUGGUUCGGGGUCACGAUGUCAAUAGGUUGCUGAAGUGGAAUUGAGGGGAAAGCUGUUGGAAUACAGAUGAACAACCAAACCUCAAGGCUGAGAUGUUGGUGAUUCAUCUUCAGGGACAUUGAAAUCACCUAGAAUCAGGUAGAUGGUUGGGUAAAACUGUGAGUCCUGCAGCAACUCACCCAAAAUGCAACAGUCCACCAUGAUUUACAAUUUAUCCUCAUCUUGAUGAGAUGGACUGACUCAUCUUACUCCAGGGCAUUCUGUAACUUGAUUGAGCUUUCUAAACAUUUUAAUCAAAUCAUUUCCCUACUCUCCAAUCAUCAGUUAUUCUAUGUGCCAUCAGACGAAACUCUAUAAAUUCCAGAUGAGUAUUGACAACCCUCUAGCAGUCAACCUAUAAUAUCAAUUUAUCUGUAGCAGUCCCUAUACUGAUCCUCCAUGACUCCCGUCAAGCCAGUCUCCUUCCCCUCCAUCAGACAGGUGUUCCUUUUGCUUUGACUCACGUUGAUCCCUCAGCCUGGAAUACUCCUCCUCUCUGAGAGGCCAAUCCAGAUCCUUCCCUUGUAGCUCAACUUGAGAUGCCUCUCUAAGUGGACAAAUCCCCCUUACCUACCUCCACCUCCUAAUCCCAUCUUGUACUACUCUUUCACCUAGAAUUAUUUUGGCAUUUAUAUACACAGAUACAGCCUCAAGCAUUUGCUUUUGUACAAAGUGAUUAAAAAAGAAUGGGUAGCUUCAAAAAUUUAUUACUCACAGAACUAUUUAUUAUAUAUGAGCAUGCAGUAUGUCAAGAAGCUCAUGUUUGUAUCCACUGGUUUUGAGGAAAUGAAGGAUGACAUUGUAACUGCUGUCUCUGCCAUCCAUGUUGCUAGGCUACAAAGGAUCUGUAGUGGACCAUGGGAUUGAUGUCUGCUGUGGGACACAAGGAACACAUAUUGAGCAUUUAUAAGAUCGUGGGAAUAACUGAGAUAGUUCCUUUACAAGUAAUAUGUUUAUAUAUAACAUAGUUACUAUGAUACGCUUUUGAAGGUGUUCAGUUUUUCUUAAAUCACCCUGCAUUGCUUCAGAACUGUCCUUGAGUUGUUUAUUGCACACAUGAUAUAGGAAACCAAAAACAAACAAAAAAAGUAAGCUAUUUAAGAACAGAAACUUUUACUUUUGUUUCCACUUAAUGCCCACUCCAGUGCUGGGAACAGAGCUAGCCUUCAAUCAGGACUUGCUGAAAGAAUAAGUUGUUAAAUUGCCAAAAUGUUUUACUUAAAUAUAGGGUAGCUCUCUCCUAUGUCUUACAUAUUUAUUUUGAAAAAAAAUAUUAAGGAUGUAAUGUUUUAACACAAACAAAUAUAGAGAUUAUGUAUAGUCCUUAGUAUCAUCCAGUAGUUCUUUCUCCUCAAAUCUUCAUUUUAAGUGAUAUCCCAAACACUUGCCUUGUUAAAGCCAAGCAAACAUUUGUCUUUAUUUCCUUGUCAGUACCAGCCUCUAUCCUUCUUUAUCCUUCAGUCUUUCUCCUCUUCUCUCCCAACCUCUCUACCCUCCUCUGUUAAGAACCUGUACAAAUUCCAACUCAGGUAGGAUGACACAUAACACAUAAUUAUUUCUUUCACUCAAGGCCUGAGGAACUAAGUCAAGUCUACGAAUCUGUUUUUGUUGCUAAUUUUUUGUUUGUGGAUUUUUAAAACACUAAAGUUGAUCAAUUUAUUUGUACGUUAUUUACAUAUGUGCAUAUACGAACACAUACAGUAUAUGCAAAAUUCAUCUUUCUGUCUCAGAAUUUAGGAGCCUAAAGGAAAGACCAUGUGCCAACCAUGAAUCUAAUACAUGACGUAUGCUACCAACAUAAACUUGCAUGCAUCAGAGGCUAUCAGAAAUAAUAUGGGAAAAUAGGUCUCUACCAAGUGACUUCAUAAGGAGUGAAUGAUAUUUUCUUGACUCUAACUCUAAUGAGAUCAUGUUUUCUUCUGGCUCAUGUCUUUGCCUGUAUGUUCUGUUUUCUACAUCUUUUUCAAAUUACCCUUCACUUUUCAGCUUUAUUCCUCUGCUUCUGUCUGACUUAAAGCUAAUGUAUGAAACGCACAAGAAUUUGGAUGGAAAAGCCCAUGGCAAGUUUUGGCAGAGGUUCCACCAGUCUUUCCAUAAAGGGCAGGAGGAAAAGUCAUUUUCAGAAUAGGUCAGGUGACAAUAUAAAUAUCGGAAAGUACAGCUUUUCUGAAUAAAGUUUUCAUGUAUUCAUUCCUUUAACAAAUAUUUAUUGGACACCUGUUGAGUGCCAAGCACUGUUCUUGGUGCCAGGUUCUCCUUGAGAAGAAGAUAAGAAUUCCUGCCAACAUUCUACCUGAGGGAGACAAUAAGUGAUUAAAUAUACGAUAAGAUGGUAAGUACUAUAGAGACAAUCAGAGCAGAGGACGGGGAGAAGGAGAGCUGGAGGAGAGUGUUUACAGUUUCAUAUAGGGUAGUCAAAGAAGGCCUUACUGGGAAGGUGACAUUUGAGCAAAGGCUUCAGGAGGUGAGGGAAGGAUGCCUAUGCGUAUCUGUAGGAGAGCAGUUCAGGCAGAGGAUAAGCAAGUACAAAGGCCCUAAGCUGGGAACACACUGAGCAUAUUUGAGGAGGAACAAGCAAGGAGGUCCGUGAGGCUGAAGUAGAACGAGCAAAGGGAAGAUUAGCGAGAGUCUUGGAAAGCUCACAAAGGGCUGCGUGGCAGGACCUGGAAGCGCAUUAUAAGGACUUUGACAUUAAUUCUGAUUGAGAUCAGGAGCCACUGAAGGCUUUUGAGUGGAGUUGUGACACACAUUAUGUGGCUUUCAUUUUAAAGGAGUCAUUCACUGCUGUGGUGAGAGGCUAUUCCAGAAAACCUGUCAGGAAAUUGUUGUGCUUUGGACCAACAUGGUAGCAAUGGAGGUGAUGGAAAGGGGUCAGAUUCUGUAUAUAUUUUAAAAAUAGAGUCAACAGAUGUCCUGAUCAAUUAUAUGUGGGGUGAGAAAGAGAGAGAUAGAUUGGAUUAAGGACGCCAAAGUUUUCAUCCUGAGGAAUGUAGUUGUCACUAUCUGAGUUGGAAGAAACACAGCAAUCAUGGGAGAAAGCAGGUUUCUGGGAGGGGGAAGUUAGGGGUUAAGUUAUAAAAUAAGUUUUAACAUUUUUUUUCUUUUGAGACAGAGUCUCGCUCUGUCACUCGAGCUGGAGUACAGUGGCACAAUCUCAGCUCACUGCAACCUCUGCCUCCCGGGUUCAAGUGAUUCUCAUGCCUCAGCUGCCCAAGUAGCUGAGAUUACAGGCUCAUGCCACCACACCCGGCUAAUUUUUGUAUUUUUAGUAGAUACAGGGUUUCACCGUGUUGGCCAGGCUGGUCUUGAACUCCCGACCUCAAGUGAUCCACCCGCCUCGGCCUCCCAAAGUGCUGGGAUUACAGCAUGAGCCACCGUGCCCAGCUUUAAAAUUUAUUUAAUUAAAUUUAUUUAUUUUGAGACAGUCUCACUUUGUCACCCAGGCAGGAGUGCAGUGGCAUGAACACAGCUCACUGUGGUCCCAACCCUCUGGGCUCAAGCGAUUCCUCCUGCCUCAGCCUCUGAAGUAGCUAGGAUUAUAGGUGUGCACAACCACACCCGGCUAAUUUUUUAUUUUUUAACUAGAGUUGGAGUCUCACUAAGUGCCCCAGGCUGGUCUCAAACUCCUGAGCUUAGGCAGUCCUCCCAUUUUGGCCUUCCAAAGUGCUAUGAUUACAGGCAUGAGCCACUGCACCCAGCCUAAUAUAAGCGUUUUUAUUCUGUGCAGGUAAAUAAAAACACUAAGGCAGUUUGUCCACUUCUGCUGUUUCUUCCCCCAAUCCUGCAAAUUUGGUCAUGUUUUUACUAGACUCUUGCUGUUGAGUUAAAACAUUCUAGAUGGCUACAGUUCAGUGAUUCUGUUUAUUCCAAUUUUAUUGAACCUAAUAUAUGAUUGCCUAAUAUGAGAUGGGAGAUUUCCUUCAGGAGUACUAAUUUGCUGAAGUGUGGUUACUCUACCUCUGGUUCAUAUUCAUAUGCAAGUCCUAAGGGCAUGAAAACUAAUAAAAUAUAAUAUUUUUUAUUUAAAGUAAAAUAUCCAUGUCUCAGGAUCCUAUCACUAAUGCCCUAAACAAAAGUUAUCUAAAUCUUAAUAACUUUUAUUCAAAUAUCAAAAUUGUGAACAUCUGUUAGAACUUGGUAAAAUACUGCAAUUAAUUUAAUAUUAUAUAUGAAACCUCCCAGAAUAUUUGGGGGUAGAUGUUUAAACCUCAAGAGUUUCUCCAAAAAUGGAAAAAUGAACGAAUCUUAGUAGGUGGUAGAAAAUCAGUUUCUUGAGUAGGAGAGAAAUUCUCUAACUGAACAAAUUUGUUGUCAUCUUUAUGGAUUUUUUUUUCUGUUAUAUUGAAGAGAGUGGAGAAAGCCUCAGAGUUUGCAGUGUCAAAUGCAUUUUUUACUAGAAAUUCAGAUUUACCUAGAAGUCCCUGGGGCCAAAUCACAGAUUUGAAAACAUCUGAGCAAAUAGAGGAUCAUGAUGAAAUCUAUGCAGAAGGAGCUGGUCAAUGACUGGUUAGACACCAAACUUAAGCAAGAAUUAGCAAGUGAGGAAGAAGGUGAUGCUAAAAACACUGUGUCAAGUGUCACUAUUAUGCCGGAAGCCAAUGGCCAUUUGAAAUAUGACAAGUUUGAUGAUUUAUGUGGCUAUUUGGAGGAAGAAGAGGAAAGUACCACCGUUCAAAAAUUUAUAGACCAUCUGCUCCAUAAAAAUGUGGUAGAUUCUGCAAUGAUGGAAGAUCUUGGAAGGAAGGAAAACCAAGACAAGAAGCAGCAGAAGGAUCCUCGUCUUACCAUGGAGAUGAGACAUAAGCAGGUAAAAGAAAAUCGCUUAAGACGUGAGAAAGAACUGGAGUACCAGAGAAUAGAAAAGACCCUGAAAAAAUCGGCCUUCUUGGAGGCUCAGUGUCUGGUGCAAGAAGAGAAGAAAAGGAAGGCUCUGGAGGCCAAGAAAGAGGAAGAGGAGAUUCAAAGGGAGAUGGUGAAGCUGCGGAGGGAGAUAAUUGAGAGGAGACGCACUGUGAAAGCAGCAUGGAAAAUAGAGAAGAAAAGGCAAGAAGAGAAUUCUCAAAAUAGUUCAGAAAAAGUCAUGUUUCAAAGUACUCACAUUCUUCCAGAUGAGGAAAAAAUGGUGAAGGAAAGAAAAAGGAAAUUGAAAGAAGUAUUAAUCCAAACUUUCAAAGAAAAUCAACAGUGUCAAAAACGGUAUUUCGCUGCCUGGCACAAGCUGAUUCUUGAUCAUAGGAUUAAGCUGGGGAAAGCUGGGACCCUGUCUGACUGGAAGAUUCAGCUGAAGGUCCUGCGGGCCUGGAGAGACUACACAAGAUUCCAGAAGUUGGAGCGGGAGACUCAAGCCUUGGAAAAUGAUCUUAGGGAAGAAAACAGAAAACAACAACUGGCCACUGAGUAUAACCGGAAACAAGUUCUCCGACACUGCUUUACAGAAUGGCAGCAUUGGCAUGGCGCCGAGCUCCUGAAGAGAGAGCUGGCUCUCACAAAAGAGGAAACUAGGAAGAAGAUGGAUGCACUGCUGCAGGCAGCAUCACUGGGGAAACUCAGUGCCAAUGGGUUAUCAGGCAUCAGUCUACCUGAGGAGGCAACAGCCAUGGUGGGUCCACCAGUAAAAAAUGGACAGGAGACUGCUGUGCCCCCUUUGUGGGAAAAGCCUCCCUUGGGAAGCAGUGGUUGUAUGCUCAGUCCUCCCCUGGGAAGAACAACAACAGGCAACUUGCAGGGUUCCCUUCAGAAUGUCUCUCUGAGUGCACCUGGCAAUAAGCAGCACAAGACCCUGGGUGCUGAACCCUCUCAACAGCCUGGCAGCAACGAGACACUCAGAACUACCAGCCAGAAAGCAGAACCGCUUUGCUUGGGUCAUUUCCACAACCGCCAUGUCUUCCAGCAACAGCUGAUUGAGAAGCAAAAGAAGAAACUUCAGGAACAGCAGAAAACAAUUCUCGAGCUGAAGAAAAACCUGCAGCUGGCAGAGGCUCAGUGGGCAGCAGAGCAUGCCUUAGCAGUCACAGAAGCACAGAGCCACCUGCUGUCAAAGCCCAGAGAAGAGGAACCAAGAACCUGCCAGAUGCUUGUGAAUUCACCUGUUGCUUCCCCUGGGACUGAAGGCAGAAGUGACUCCCGAAAUUCUCUUUCUGGACUCAGAAGGAAACCAAAGCAAUUGAUGACACCGCAUCCCAUACUAAAAGCUAUGGAAGAGAGAGCAAUUCAACGAGCUGAAUGUAGGCGGAUCUUGGCAGAGAAGAAGAAAAAACAAGAAGAAGAAAAAUUGGCCCAGUUAAAGGCCCAAGAGGAGGAACGUCAGAAAAGGGAGGCAGAAGAAAAGGAGGCACAGCUUGAAAGAAAACGAGAAGAGAAGAGACUGAAGAAAAUGAAAGAACUUGAGAAGCAGAAGAGAAUUAAGAGGAACCAGCAGCUGGAAGCAAUAGCCAAAGAACAUUAUGAAAGGGUCUUGCUAAGGAAAAAAGGUCUAGAGCCUUGGAAGAGAUUGAGAAUGCAAAGCAAACAAAACAUCCAGGUGGCAGAAGAACAUUACUCUUUGUUCCUGCAGAGGAAAUACAUGCUGACGUGGUUCCAGCGUAGUCAGGAAAGUCUGGCUAGAAAGAUGGCCCAGGCUGAUCAAUUUUAUUCCCAAAUACUGCUUAAGAGAGUCAUCCAGAGCUGGCUACAGUACGUGAUUGAUCUGCAGGAAGAAGUAAGAAAAUUUUGUGUACAUUUUCUUCAAAAGAAGAUUUUCAGGGCCUGGUUUAACAUGGUCAGGGAGGUGAAGAUCGAUUCUCAGGGCAAGCAUGAGAUUGCAGCGGAGCACAGUGACAGGAGGAUCCUCUGGAUCACCCUUCGGACAUGGAAGAAGUUUGUAAAAUUUAUGAAAGAGGAAAGAGUAAAAGAAGAAAGGCGACAGCAACUUCGUAGGAAGGUAGUUGAAAUUCUUCCAGACUUCCAGGUACCUGGAAGGUACCACGAGCUAUAUCAGCAAUCAGAUACUUGGUCCUUGAGUAAGACAAGUCUGGUGAACGAAUGAGCCAGAUUAGUGUAAUAUUUAGGACAGGAAGCUCGACUAGUCUGUAUGUGUGUUAUCUCCACCCACCCACACACAUACAUACAUACACCUGGUUUAUUCUCUACGAGCUACUUCUUAGAUCAAAGGAAUUAUUUUGAGAAUUUUUAUUCCCUUCUUUGACUUUUCCUGGAUUGCUAGUCAUUCACUAUAGCAUUUAUCACAGUGGGAUCAUCCAAAGGAACAUUCUAGAGAUCGUCUGUUCAAAUAUAUCCUAUAUAUUUUUAGCAUAGUAAACUUUAAAAAGGACAAGUGUUUGCCUGACUGAGCCUGUGAAGAAAAUGUGUCCGUAUAGCACGACAGGAGUUGCUGAUGUGACCUUAAUGAAACAGAAAUAAACAGGGGUGAGUGCUCGGAAAGGAAGGGCGGGCCAAGGCACUCAGCCUUCUAGUGCAGUAGCAUCAGUGACACGCACCCCACCAGACCUCGUCCACUUUCACCACCCCUGAAGGCAGACCAUGUAUGAAAAGGUUCUCUACACAGCUGCUGCAGAGGACAGCAGCUUAUCCUGAUUUCAGAGAAACUGAGGCACCAGAGAUGCUUCUCUUCCGUGCACCUUGAUAAGCAUGAAGGACAUUCCAAAAGGUAAUAGCUCUAUCAUGACAGUCCAGCAAUUCAUUAAAUUAUCUGUUCAUGCUCCCACCUGCAACUGCUGAAUAAUACACUCAGUUUGUCUUCUAGUACUCAGCUCAGUUUGAUCUAGAUAUUGAGAUACCUAUCUUGAAUUCAAAGAAUGUUUUCAUCUUUAAGAUGCUAUAAAGACUGAUAAAAUGCUCUCUUCUAUGAAUUGUGUUAGAGAAUUACCUGCUAGAAAAAUAAUUUUUCAUUAUAAAAUACACAUUUAUUAUAUAACAAAUUCAAGUAGUCCAUAAAUGCAUAUGGUAAAAUGAGAAAGUCCUGUGCAGUCCUGAGAUGAUUACUCUUAUUUGGUGUGCUGAAAAUUUGAGUUGACAAAAUAAAAUUCUGUGGUUUUUUAAGUGAA